CCUUUUGUUUGUCUCACGUUUUGCGUGGGAGGCGGUCCCGGGAUUUCAGGGGUCUACCGGCUCUCUUAUGGCGAAUGCAACCCGAAGAGAGAGUGAGCUGUAUCUUCAGAGUUGUCUCCGUCUUUCCAAGAACAGAACAAAAUGAACAAGGUAGAUCAGAAGUUCCAGGGGUCAGUAUCAUUUAAAGAUGUGACUGUGGGCUUCACCCAGGAGGAGUGGCAGCACCUGGACCCUAGUCAGAGGGCUCUGUAUAGAGAUGUGAUGCUGGAGAACUACAGCAACCUUGUCUCAGUGGGGUAUUGUGCUCACAAACCAGAGGUGAUCUUCAGGCUGGAACAAGGAGAAGAACCAUGGAGACUGGAGGAAGAAUUCCCAAGCCAGAGCUUUCCAGGCUCCUCUUGGCUAUGGUGGUUUCCCAGACUUUCCUUGUUUUGGAUGACCUUGACAGUUUGGAGGAAUCCUGGUGAGAGCACUUUCUUUCUGUCACUGCAAGAUGGUCCAGGCUUAUCUUAUAUAUUUCCUUUCUGAAAUCAGUCACCAUUUCUUCAGAAGUCUGGACAGCUGAUCACCUGAAAGAGAGGAGCCAAGAAAAUCAAUCUAAACAUUUGUGGGAAGUUGUAUUCAUCAAUAAUGAAAUGCUGACUAAGGAACAAGGUAAUGUAAUAGGAAUACCAUUUAACAUGGACGUAAGUUCUUUUCCUUCCAGAAAAAUGUUCUGUCAGUAUGACUCACGUGGAAUGAGUUUCAACACUGUUUCAGAAUUGGUUAUCAGUAAGAUAAACUAUUUAGGAAAAAAGUCUGACGAAUUUAAUGCAUGUGGGAAAUUGUUACUCAAUAUUAAGCAUGAUGAAACUCAUACUCGAGAGAAAAAUGAAGUUUUGAAAAAUAGGAACACUCUGAGUCAUCGUGAGAACACUUUGCAGCAUGAGAAGAUUCAAACUUUAGACCACAAUUUUGAAUACAGUAUAUGUCAGGAAACCCUCCUUGAAAAGGCAGUAUUCAAUACACGGAAGAGAGAGAAUGCAGAAGAGAAUAACUGUGACUAUAAUGAAUUUGGGAGAACUUUCUGUGAUAGUUCAUCCCUCUUGUUCCAUCAGAUACCUCCAUCAAAGGACAGUCACUAUGAAUUUAGUGAUUGUGAGAAGUUCUUAUGUGUGAAGUCCACCCUUUCUAAACAUGAUGGGGUACCUGUGAAACACUAUGAUUGUGGUGAAAGUGGGAAUAAUUUCAGGAGGAAAUUGUGUCUGUCACAGCUUCAGAAAGGUGAUAAAGGAGAGAAACACUUUGAAUGUAAUGAAUGUGGGAAAGCUUUCUGGGAGAAGUCACAUCUCACUCGACAUCAGAGGGUGCACACAGGAGAGAAACACUUUCAAUGUAAUCAAUGUGGAAAAACUUUCUGGGAGAAGUCAAACCUCACUAAACAUCAGAGAUCACACACAGGGGAGAAACCUUUUGAAUGCAAUGAAUGUGGGAAAGCCUUUAGCCAUAAGUCAGCCCUCACAUUACACCAGAGAACACAUACAGGGGAGAAACCCUAUCAGUGUAAUGCAUGUGGGAAAACUUUUUACCAGAAAUCUGACCUCACUAAACAUCAGAGAACACACACAGGGCAGAAACCCUAUGAAUGUUAUGAAUGUGGAAAAUCCUUCUGUAUGAAUUCACACCUUACAGUACACCAGAGAACUCACACAGGUGAGAAACCUUUUGAAUGUCUUGAGUGUGGGAAAUCCUUUUGUCAAAAGUCACAUCUUACACAGCAUCAGAGAACUCACAUAGGAGAUAAACCUUAUGAAUGUAAUGCAUGUGGGAAAACUUUCUACCACAAGUCAGUACUCACCAGGCAUCAGAUAAUUCAUACAGGGUUGAAACCUUAUGAAUGUUAUGAAUGUGGGAAAACCUUCUGCUUGAAGUCAGACCUCACAAUACAUCAGAGAACGCACACAGGGGAGAAACCCUUUGCAUGUCCUGAAUGUGGGAAAUUCUUUAGCCAUAAGUCAACCCUCUCUCAACAUUAUAGAACACACACGGGGGAGAAACCCUAUGAAUGUCAUGAAUGUGGAAAAAUCUUUUACAAUAAAUCAUACCUAACAAAACAUAAUAGAACACAUACAGGGGAGAAACCCUAUGAAUGUAAUGAAUGUGGAAAAACCUUCUGCCAGAAGUCACAACUCACUCAGCAUCAGAGAAUUCACAUAGGGGAGAAACCCUAUGAAUGUAAUGAGUGUGGAAAAGCUUUCUGCCAUAAGUCAGCUCUAAUUGUACAUCAGAGAACCCAUACACAAGAAAAGCCUUAUAAAUGUAACGAAUGUGGAAAAUCUUUCUGUGUGAAGUCAGGACUUAUUUUACAUGAGAGAAAGCACACGGGGGAGAAACCCUAUGAAUGCAAUGAAUGUGGGAAAUCCUUCAGUCACAAAUCAUCACUCACAGUACAUCACAGGGCUCACACAGGAGAGAAAUCUUGUCAGUGUAAUGAAUGUGGAAAAAUCUUUUACCGUAAAUCAGACCUUGCUAAACAUCAGAGAUCACAUACAGGGGAAAAGCCCUAUGAAUGUAACACAUGCAGGAAAACCUUCUCUCAAAAGUCAAAUCUCAUUGUACAUCAGAGAACACACAUAGGAGAAAAACCUUAUGAAUGAAUUGGAUAUUAGAAAUUUCCAGCCACAAGUCAGCCUCCAUAAUGCCUCAGAGUCUUCACACUGUGGAGAAGGGCCUGUUGACAUCCUGAAUGUUCAAUAACUAUCCACAAACUCGCCUUAUGUUACUCCAAAGUAACAGUAGGGGAUAAACCCAUAGACUACAACAACUAUAGGAUGGCUUUUGUUAGGAAGUGAUAUUCUGUUGAAUAUCAGAUGGUUAAUACUGGCAUAAAACCUCACAGAUUUUUUUGAAUUUGUGAAAGUUUUUGGCAAAACUACAAAUAGGAUUAUGUUAGCAUUUACACUGAGGAGAAAAUUGUCAAUUUAAGAAAUCUAAAGUGAAAAUUUUGCUUAGAAAUAAAAUAUGACAAGUUCUGUUUUGAGUUUGAUGCCAUAAUAGUUUUUAAGGUAUCUAACAAUAAUUUAUAGAUGUACAUUGUGGAAUGUAAAGCUUUAAGAAUUUUUUAAGAAGUAAUAAUUAAAAUAACCUCACAAGAAGUUGUAAUGAGUACAGAGAAUUCCCGUGUACCCUUCACCAAGCUUCCUCUAAGGAUAAUAUAUAAUCAUAGUAUAUGGUCAAGUCCAAGAAAUCGAUGUUACCUUGCUAGUAGAUGCAGACUUACUCAGAUUUUGCUAUGGUUUGCGUGCACUCUGUGUGUGUACGUGUAUGUGUGUGUGUGUGGUUAUAACAAACUGGUACUUUUACAUUUGAGUAACCAUCAACACAAUUAGUUUACAGAAUGGAAAAGGAGUCUGAGAUCUGUACUGUUUCAGGAUUACAAAGGAAUCAGGAUUUAGCCUCAAGUAGUUCCCUUGUUGUAUUAAUAACCACACCCUUUCUGCAUCCCUGUCCCUGGCAUCCACUUGACUAUGAAGCUUUUUGUAAAGCAUAGAUAAAUUGAAUAAUCAGGGCAACAGCAUUAAGCACAUCUGUGAAUUAUCCCUGAAGUUCAUAGGACUUACAUAUGUACAAGUGGUAUGUGAUAUAAAUCGUGUGUUUCAUAUGCAUAAUGGUAUUUAACGUAAUUGUGAAUAGGAAGUAGGUAUCCUAAUUUAGUAGUGGUUACUUCAUCAGGCCCAUCCCAGGUGUUUGUCGUGUCCUGAAACAAUUUAAAUAGAGACCCACAGAGCUAAUGUUUAUCCAUUUAAAAGUUAUAAAUCAAAAUAACAGAUUAUCUGAAAAAAAAUCUAUCCUGUACGUGUGAAGAUCUAGGCCUGCCUCCAUGUUACUCCCUUUCUCUUACUACCUGUGGCUCAUCCCAUGCCAUGAACUGCCUGGGGUACAUAUGUGAACACUCCAGCCUUCAGCGUAAGUGAUAGUCCAAAUUUUCUUUAAGCAGCUGCUCUCCAAGACAGGGCCCUGGAAAGAGGCCCACACAUACAGCCCAGUUGCUGCCCAGGGCUGUUGGACUGUCAUUUCAUUGCUCAUUGUACCCAGACAGGGAUCUGGGCCUUCAGAGACUUUUGAGAAUAUGAAGAGGAGGGUUGAGGCUGGAGAAGAGCCAGAAUCAAGCUGGCAUGGGGCUUUUAUUGACAGUGUGAAGAUUGUACACUACAUUACAUGAUCAGAUCAUACAAAUAAUCUAAGAUUUUACAGUCUGGUGACCCUAGAUUACACAAGUAAUCUAAGCUUCCACUUUGGAAAACUAGAAAAAGAAGAGCAAAUUAAAUCCAAAGUAACCUGGAAAAAAAUUAGAGUAAAAAUCAGUGAAAUUGAAAAGAGAAAAUCAAUAAAACCCAAAACUGUUCUUUGAAAAGGUGGGUAAAAUUGAUAAACCUCUAGCUAGAUUAAGAAAAAACAGAAGACAAAUACUGCUAAUACCAAAAGUGAAAGAGGCCAUCAUAGCUGAUCCUAUGGUCACCAAAAGGAUUAGAAAGAAAUAUGGACAACUCUGUCCAUAAAUUUGAUAACUUAGCUAAAAUGGAUCAAUUCCUUGCAAGAUGCAUUCUCUCAAAGCUCAUAAAAGGUAGAUCUCAGUAGGCAUAUAUAUCUAUUAAAUAAAUUGAAGCAGUAAUUAAUAACCUUCCAAGACCAGGCGCGGUGGCUAAAAAUACAAAAAGUUAGCCGGGCGUGGUGGCAUGCGUGUAUAGUCCAAGCUACUCAGGAGGCUGAGGCAGAAGAAUCACUUGAACCUGGGAGGUGGAGGUUGCAGUGAGCCAAGAUUGUGCCACUGUACUCCAGCCUGGGUGACAGAGUGAGACUCCAUCUCAAUAAAAUUAAUAAUAAUAAAACCUUCCAAAAAAAGUGCCGGGACCAAAUGGAUUCACUGAUGUGCAUUUUUCGAGAUACUUAAGGUAGAAAUGAUACCAAGUCUGUACUGUCUCUUUCAGAAAAUAAAAGCAGGGAUAACACUUCCCAAAUCAUUUUGUGAGGCCAGGAUUACCCUAAUACCAAAGCCAGGCAAAAACAUUACAAGAAAGGAAAACUACAGAUCAAUAUUUCCAGUGAACACAGAUGCAGAAAUCCUUAAAAUGUUAGCAAAUCAGGAAUGCAAGCCUUGUUCAACAUUUGAUAUUCAGUGCAAUCCAUUGCAUGCAUUAGCAGUUCAAAGAUUAAAUAUGAUCAUAUCAAUAGGUACAGAAAAAGCAUUUGACAAAAUCCAAUAUCCAUUCAUGAUAAAACCUCUCAACACAGAAGGAAUACAGGAGAACUUACUCAAUUUGAUAAAGAACUACUACAAAAAACCCUACAUCUAGCAUCAUCCUUGAUGUUUCCAACUAAAUGCUUUCCUACUAAGAUCAGGAACAUGGCAAGGAACACCACUGCUUUUCAGCAUUGUACUGGAAGUGCUAUCUAAUGCAGUGAUACCAAAAAAAAAGGAAAUAAAAUGCACAUAAAUUUGGAAGGAGGAAAUACAACUGUCUUUGUUCUCAAAUAACAUGAUUGUCUUUGUAGAAAAUUCUAAAUAACAAAAACCUGCUGACAUUAAUAAGCAAUUAUAGCAGGGUUGUAGAAUGUAGUCCUCAGGUAUAUGAUAAAAAAGAAUUAGACAUCAAGUCAUUAAAAGACAUAUAGGAACCCUAAAUGCUUAUUGUUAAGUGAAAACCAAUCUGAAAAGGCUUUCUAUGUUGUAUGAUUGCAAUUAUAUGACAUUCUGGGAGAGGCAAAACUAUCGAGCGAGUCAAAGGACCAGUGGUUGCUGAGAGUUGAGGGGAAAGGAGGGAUGGCAGGUAGGUGAUUUUUAGGACAGUGAAAGUACUCUGUAGGGUACUGUAAUUUGUCAAAAUGCAGAGAAUGGAAAACAGUGAACGGAAAACACAGAGUAAACCCUAGUGUCAACUCUGGACUUCAGUUAAUAACAGUGUACCACUAUUGGCUCAUCAAUUGUAACAAAUGAACCAUAAUGAUGCAAGAUGUUAAUAAUUGGGGAGCCUGUGGAGGAUGGGAGGGUUAAAGGUUUAUAUGAGAAUUCUCUGUACUUUUUGCUCAAUUUUUCUGUAACCCUAAAGCUGCUCUAAAAAAUGAAGUGUAUUAAGUAAAUAAAUAAGUAAAUAACCAACCAA